GAAGACAUAGCUGCGGGUGGCUGUGCUGGUGGCGUUCAAGAUGUCGACCAAGAAUUUCCGAGUCAGUGACGGGGACUGGAUUUGCCCUGACAAAAAAUGUGGAAAUGUAAACUUUGCUAGAAGAACCAGCUGUAAUCGAUGUGGUCGGGAGAAAACAACUGAGGCCAAGAUGAUGAAAGCUGGGGGCACUGAAAUAGGAAAGACACUUGCAGAAAAGAGCCGAGGCCUAUUUAGUGCUAAUGACUGGCAAUGUAAAACUUGCAGCAAUGUGAAUUGGGCCAGAAGAUCAGAGUGUAAUAUGUGUAAUACUCCAAAGUAUGCUAAAUUAGAAGAAAGAACAGGAUAUGGUGGUGGUUUUAAUGAAAGAGAAAAUGUUGAAUAUAUAGAAAGAGAAGAAUCUGAUGGUGAAUAUGAUGAGUUUGGACGUAAAAAGAAAAAAUACAGAGGGAAAGCAGUUGGUCCUGCAUCUAUAUUAAAGGAAGUUGAAGAUAAAGAAUCAGAGGGAGAAGAAGAGGAUGAGGAUGAAGAUCUUUCUAAAUAUAAGUUAGAUGAGGAUGAGGAUGAAGAUGACGCUGAUCUCUCAAAAUAUAAUCUUGAUGCCAGUGAAGAAGAAGAUAGUAAUAAAAAGAAAUCUAAUAGACGAAGUCGCUCAAAGUCUCGAUCUUCACAUUCACGAUCUUCAUCACGCUCAUCCUCCCCCUCAAGUUCAAGGUCUAGGUCCAGGUCCCGUUCAAGAAGUUCUUCCAGUUCGCAGUCAAGAUCUCGUUCCAGUUCCAGAGAACGUUCGAGAUCUCGUGGGUCGAAAUCAAGAUCCAGCUCCAGGUCCCACAGGGGCUCUUCUUCCCCACGAAAAAGAUCUUAUUCAAGUUCAUCAUCUUCUCCUGAGAGGAACAGAAAGAGAAGUCGUUCUAGAUCUUCUUCAUCUGGUGAUCGCAAAAAAAGACGAACAAGAUCACGGUCACCCGAAAGCCAGGUGAUUGGUGAAAACACUAAACAACCCUGAGCCCAGGGCCAACCCCUACGGAACACCACUACUUUACCCAGGUUGAUAUUGACUUAUUCAUACUAGCUGCAUGAAUAUAACCCUAUAGCAAAUUGUACAAUCAUCUUGUGUGACCUAGAUUUCCAAAACUUAUUUAUGAGUAUAUUUUCUCAUACACAGAAGCCUUGCUGUAUCUUUUUUACAUAAUAGACUUCUUACACUUUCUACACCGUGUCACAGGGAUUGGUUUAGUCACACUUCCAUUACCAAGUUUAUAUGCUUUUGUUGUACAUUUUCUGUAAUUUUACACAUUUUUGCAAGGCUUUUCUUUGAUAUCUUAAAUAAUUGAGAGGUGGCUAUAUUUUGAAAUGAGAUUCUUUUGAAAUUGUAGAGAAUUUUUUAUUGUAUUUAUAUGAUAACUGGGCUCAUAUCCAAAGUCUAAACAUCAGAUAAUUUUAUGUGUGUAAGUUCCUAUCUCAAUUUUUAAUUUUUUUGCUAGCAUCAUGGUACUGAAUUUUGUAUACUUUCACAGUCUUAAGAAUGAAUGCUGAGAUUUAGCUCUAGCUUACUAGAAUGCCUACUCUCUCCAUUAUGUCUUACAGACGCCACAGGUCAUCAUCUGGAUCAUCCCAUUCUGGUUCCCGUUCAAGUUCAAAAAAGAAAUAAUGUAUUAAAAUUUACAUCUUAAAAAAAUCCAGUACAGUGCAUGAAGCAUAUUUUUAAAGAAGUUGGUGUCUUACUUGGUCAGAAGUGCUAAAUCUGCUAGUAGAGGUGCAUGCCUUUCAUUGCUUUUCAAAACAAUACAGCUGUGUUUAUUUGUGAAGUUAAAAGUAAAUAGCAUUUUAAGCCAUAAUGUCCCAAAAUAGAUGUUCUGUCAUUCAUUAUUUACAACCAUUUGCUUCAUUUAAAACCAUUUCAGCUAUAACAAAGUACUUUGCUUCCUAAUUUAAACCCAUUUUUGUCAUUUCCAAAUACAUCCUGUCCAUUGGCUAAGACAGGAUUACCUAGGCUUGCCUGAACUUUGGGCAUGGAAGAAAGACUGGAAACUAGUUGGAAACAACAUACUUAUGGAAAAGAAAGUCAGCCUUUUUAUGCUGUUAACAGAUGUCAGAGUGAUUCUCACCAAAAAAAGUUAAACUAUGUUGUAAGCAGCCAACUGUAAAUGUCUAUUUUGAAAUUCCCUAUGCUAAGGGUGCCUUAGAAUCAUUGUGUCUCUUUUAUCCAGCUUUACUUUUUUGCUCCACAUUUAAUGCAAAAGAAUCUUGUGAUGUCUACAAGGAGAGAAGUGGGAUAUAUUUUCCUUUCUGACACAUAAUUUGGGGCAAAAAAGAAAGUCUUAAGAGUUUAUCUUUUCUCUGCUGAUACGGUUGCUUGAUAAAGACAUCUCAAAAUGUUUACCAAUGUUUUAAGAAGCUUUGUGUGAUAUUCUUCCAAAUGUAGUUACCAAAUAUAAUAUGGUAGAAAAGGCUAAAUCAUACUUAAUGAGCAAAUUGAAGUAAGCUUUUAAAGUAUAUUUCUCUUUUGGUGAAAGGCCAAUGGAGACAUUGUGAAUUUAAGUGAACAUUUGCCUCAAGAUGUUAACUAUAAACACACUGCAUACAAUUUUCUUCUGAAUAACAAAUGAAUGCUUAUUGCUGCAUGAUGUAAGCAAAAGUCAUUAUUUUUCCUAUUCAUUUGAAAUAAGUUAUGGCUUAAAAUGCUUUUGGAGUUUAUUUCUCAAAAUUAAAAUCUGGUCACAUGAGCUUUAGUUUGUUUUCUGGUUUAAAAAAUAAAAAGGUUUCUCUUAACAGUAUUUCCAGUGACAAUGCAAGGUAAGUAUAUCAAAGGAAAUCAACAGUUGUGCUUGGGGGCUUUUUGUUAUGGGAUAUUGAUUUCUUGUUUUUUUUCCGUAACAUUGUCUGCUGCAAUUUAAAUAAAAAUUACGACAUUUUAAGAUAUUUCAUAGACAAACCAAACAAAAAUAUAUGUUUUUACUUUAAAGUGAAUGUUUUUCUCUUCAGCUGAUCUAAAAAUGAAAGCAAGAUAUCUUAUGUAGAAAUAUUUUGAUAAUAUUUUUACAGUGAGCUUUCCCAUGUUUUUAUGUCUUAAGUUUCUUUGCUGCGUUUAUGUAGGUUGCACAAGAACUUUUACUCACUUGUAAUUGUGCCUCAGACUUUUUGAAAGUCUACCUUCUAAAUUGCCCCGACGAUCUAGAUUCUACAUGUUACCAUUGGUUUAUUCUUGUGCUUUCUGUAUUUAAAACUUUGGCUGUACUAAGCAAAUGCAAGGUUAUAAUUUAGCUAAUAGUAGUUUACAGACAAUUCUGAUGAUUAUGAUUUCAUUUGGUUUAACUAAGCUGUACUAGUUCAUUUCAUAAGGAAAUGAUACUGUAGACAAAUGUAAAUAAAGCCUGUGAGUCAAGCAUCAAGUGGUGUUUGUUAGAAAUAAACUAGAGAUUUUUAAACUCUGA